GCUCUGGGGCCGGUACUUGCGCGCCCGCACCCCGCGCUCCCCGCCCCGCUCCCCGUCCCGCGCUCCACGCGCGCCCCAGCGUUGGGGGCUUCUCCUCCGCGGCGGGAAUGUCUGGCCGGCUCCGGCAGCACGGCGCGGCCCAGGUCCCCGCGCCCACGACGGGCCAGCGCGCUGGGCCAUGAUCCGGCUGGGCGGCUGGUGUGCGCGGCGGCUCUGCAGCGCGGCGGUUCCCGCGGGGCGGCGCGGGGCGGCGGGCGGGCUGGGCCUGGCGGGAGGCCGCGCCCUACGGGUGCUGGUGGACAUGGACGGCGUGCUGGCUGACUUCGAGGGCGGAUUCCUCAGGAAGUUCCGCGCGCGCUUUCCCGACCAGCCCUUCAUCGCGCUGGAGGACCGGCGCGGCUUCUGGGUGUCGGAGCAGUACGGCCGCCUGCGGCCAGGGCUGAGCGAGAAGGCCAUCAGCAUUUGGGAGUCAAAGAAUUUCUUUUUUGAACUUGAGCCUCUGCCAGGGGCCGUGGAAGCUGUCAAGGAGAUGGCCAGCCUACAAAACACUGACGUCUUCAUCUGCACAAGCCCCAUCAAGAUGUUCAAGUACUGUCCCUAUGAGAAGAGAUGGGGUCUUGCUAUGUUGCCCAAGCUGGUCUUGAACCCCUGGACUCAAGCAAUCCUCCUGCCUUGGCCUCCCAAAGUGCUGAGGUUACAGUAUGCCUGGGUGGAGAAGUACUUUGGCCCUGACUUUCUGGAGCAGAUUGUGCUGACCAGAGACAAGACCGUGGUCUCUGCUGACCUUCUCAUAGACGACCGGCCGGACAUCACAGGCAAGUGGCCUGCGACAGCAACAAAACCCAUUUUUUCCCCCAAAAGCAAUGUGGACUGAUGCAAUGAAUGACAGGAGGGCAGAGCAGAGCUCCUGCAGGGAAGGGGCCGAGCCAACCCCCAGCUGGGAGCAUGUCCUCUUCACCGCCUGCCACAACCAGCACCUGCAGCUGCAGCCCCCCCGCCGCAGGCUGCACUCGUGGGCGGACGACUGGAAGGCCAUUCUGGACAGCAAGCGGCCCUGCUGAGCUGGACUGUGCUUCGGGCUCCUCUGUGGGGCUCUGACCUCAGGGCUCCCAGCUCGGGGCCUGUGGGGCCAGUAUGCUGGUCUGGGAGUCCCUCCUAGACUCCUGGGCCCCAUGACCUCCUGCUGCAUGUCCCUUCCCUUCCCCAGCCCUGCCAGGCCUUAACCUGAUCACGGGGCAGGGCUGGGCCCUCUGGGCGCUUGGACAUAGACACGUGGUCCCAGGCCGUUCAGCCUGACCUCAGGCAGCAGGCACCAAGCUGCCAGAAGCCCAGGGGCUCAGGACAGGGAGGAGUUGAGGCCACUGUUCAGGGGGCUGGUGGCCGUCUCCACUCCCUAGGCAAGUUCUCUGAGGCAGAAGGGGGUUCCCUGUUCCCAGAGUCUGCAGCCAUCAGCAAGGAGGACCAGGAACCCGGCGACUGAGGUGCUUCCAGGUGGGGACAAGCCCCUCUUGGUCUCAGCCACAGCACCCCUUAUUCCAGCUGCCCUGCCCAACCUGCUCACCCCACAUGACCUUCUGUGUAUUCAGCAAACACUCACUAGGUGACAGCGGCCACCAGGCUCUGUGCUGGGGGACGAUACUGGCCCUGGCCUCGACCAGCUUAGAGGUUUCUCACACCUCUGUUCCCAGGGCCCCGCUCAGGGCCCAGCAGAGAGUCCGUAGGCUUGAACAUGUGUUGAGUGCAUGAAAAAUAAAUGCUGUUCAUGUGUGUAGCUCAA